GAGCAUGUUGGCCUGGUCCUUUGCUAGGUACUGUAGAGCAGGUGAGAGAGUGAGGGGGAAGGACUCCAAAUUAGACCAGUUCUUAGCCAUGAAGCAGAGACUCUGAAGCCAGACUACCUGGGUCCCAAUCUUGGGCUUGGUAUUUCCUCGCUGUGUGACUCUGGAUGGAGGCUCGCUCUGUUGCCAGGCUGGAGUACAGCGAUCUCGGCUCACUGCAACCUCUGCCUCCCGGGUUCAAGUGAUUCUCCUGCCUCAGCCUCCCAAGUAGCUGGGACUACAGACUGCGCCAUGGGGCUCAGCGACGGGGAAUGGCAGUUGGUGCUGAACGUCUGGGGGAAGGUGGAGGCUGACAUCCCAGGCCAUGGGCAGGAAGUCCUCAUCAGGCUCUUUAAGGGUCACCCAGAGACUCUGGAGAAGUUUGACAAGUUCAAGCACCUGAAGUCAGAGGACGAGAUGAAGGCGUCUGAGGACUUAAAGAAGCAUGGUGCCACCGUGCUCACCGCCCUGGGUGGCAUCCUUAAGAAGAAGGGGCAUCAUGAGGCAGAGAUUAAGCCCCUGGCACAGUCGCAUGCCACCAAGCACAAGAUCCCCGUGAAGUACCUGGAGUUCAUCUCGGAAUGCAUCAUCCAGGUUCUGCAGAGCAAGCAUCCCGGGGACUUUGGUGCUGAUGCCCAGGGGGCCAUGAACAAGGCCCUGGAGCUGUUCCGGAAGGACAUGGCCUCCAACUACAAGGAGCUGGGCUUCCAGGGCUAGGCCCCUGCCGCUCCCACCCCCACCCAUCUGGGCCCCGGGUUCAAGAGAGAGCGGGGUCUGAUCUCGUGUAGCCAUAUAGAGUUUGCUUCUGAGUGUCUGCUUUGUUUAGUAGAGGUGGGCAGGAGGAGCUGAGGGGCUGGGGCUGGGGUGUUGAAGUUGGCUUUGCAUGCCCAGCGAUGCGCCUCCCUGUGGGAUGUCAUCACCCUGGGAACCGGGAGUGGCCCUUGGCUCACUGUGUUCUGCAUGGUUUGGAUCUGAAUUAAUUGUCCUUUCUUCUAAAUCCCAACCGAACUUCUUCCAACCUCCAAACUGGCUGUAACCCCAAAUCCAAGCCAUUAACUACACCUGACAGUAGCAAUUGUCUGAUUAAUCACUGGCCCCUUGAAGACAGCAGAAUGUCCCUUUGCAAUGAGGAGGAGAUCUGGGCUGGGCGGGCCAGCUGGGGAAGCAUUUGACUAUCUGGAACUUGUGUGUGCCUCCUCAGGUAUGGCAGUGACUCACCUGGUUUUAAUAAAACAACCUGCAACAUCUCA